CUCGGAAAGCCACUACAUUAGCCUUCAUUUCAACUAAAAUUUGUAUCAAGGUAAUACUUUUUAAAGCGGCGAUAGGGAAUAUACUGAAACAUUUAGAAGACAGAGAUGUAUUCUGAAAUAUAUAAAAAUAUAAUGAAGGAAAUACAGAAAUAAUUGAUUUAUAAGAUAGAUGCAUCAGCGGAUAGCUAGACACAAUGGAAUGUUAUCCAGCCUCAUAAAAGAAGGAGAUACUGCCACACUGCCAUUUGUGACAUUACGGAUGAACCUGGAAGGCAUUAUGGUAAAUGGAAAGAGCCAGACAGAAAAAAAAUAAUAAUUUUCUUUACUGGUGUCAUAGUUUUCUGGUUUCUUCACCUAUUUUACAGCGAAAAUACAGAAUACUUUUCUAAAGAAAAAAAUAAUGAGAAAUUCCACAGCAGUAACAGACUUUAUUCUUCUUGGAUUGACAAGUGACCCACAGUGGCAGGUUGUACUUUUCAUAUUUCUUCUUGUUACCUACAUGUUAAGUGUGACUGGGAACCUGAUCAUUAUCACCCUCACCCUUUCAGAUCCCCAUCUGCAGACUCCCAUGUAUUUCUUCCUUCGGAACUUCUCAUUCCUGGAAAUUUCAUUCACGUCUGUCUGCAUUCCCAGAUUCCUUGUCACUGUUGUGACAGGAAACAGAACCAUUUCUUAUAAUGGGUGUGUGGCUCAGCUAUUUUUUUUCAUCUUCUUGGGGGUGACAGAAUUUUACCUUCUGGCUGCCAUGUCCUAUGACCGCUGCAUGGCCAUCUGCAAACCUCUUCAUUACACAAUCAUCAUGAGCACCAGAGUGUGUACCCUUCUUGUCUUUAGCUCCUGGCUUGCAGGGUUUCUGAUCAUCUUUCCACCAGUAAUGCUUCUGCUGCAGUUGGAUUUCUGUGCCUCCAAUGUAAUUGAUCAUUUUAUCUGUGACUCUUCUCCAAUGCUGCAGCUCUCUUGCACAAACACUCACUUUCUAGAACUCAUGGCAUUUUUUUUAGCUGUGGUAACACUGAUGGUCACCUUGACAUUAGUUAUUCUCUCCUACACAAACAUCAUCCGGACAAUUCUGAAAAUUCCUUCUAUGAGUCAAAGGAAAAAAGCCUUUUCCACUUGCUCCUCCCAUAUGAUAGUUGUCUCCAUCUCUUACAGUAGCUGUAUCUUCAUGUACAUUAAGACUUCUGCCAGAGAAAGGGUGACUUUAAGCAAAGGAGUAGCUGUGCUCAAUACCUCAGUGGCUCCUCUCUUGAAUCCCUUCAUAUACACACUGAGAAAUAAGCAAGUGAAGCAAGCCUUCAAGAGCAUGGUCCAGAAGAUGAUUUUUUCUUUAAAUAAAUGAAUGUGAUUAUGUAAAAAAUGUACCCCCAAAGGCAAAGCUGAAUGAAAAACUCUCUACCCUUCUCUACAUGAACUCUUUCUAAACACCUUAUUUCACACUUUUAGUUAGACAUAGUUACAUAUCAUCAACACUUCUUAAUGAAAUUAGCCUAAAAACCAAGAUUUAGCUCUUCUAAACUAUAUAGAAAGUGUUCGCUCUCUCACCUAUGUAACUAAAUUUUAGGUAAAUUAAUAAUUACUAUGGUUUAUUGAGGGAUAGCAUUGGGAGAUAUACCUAAGGCUAGAUGACGAGUUAGUGGGUGCAGCGCACCAGCAUGGCACAUGUAUACAUAUGUAACUAACCUGCACAAUGUGCACAUGUACCUUAAAACUUAAAGUAUAAUAAAAAAUAAUAAUAAAAUAAAGGCAAAAUAGAUUCUUCAUUCAUAAAAUAGAGGUAGCUAUAAAUUAAAAACUUACUAAAACCACAUUCAACUAUGAAAUUAAUUUUAUAUGAAAUGUUUAAACUAUGUAUCUUAAUUAAUAUAUCUAAAAUUUUUUCUUCAAUGUCACCAGGAAAAACAUGUUAUAAAACUAAAAGCAUCAUUAAAAUGUCUCCUUGUAUUUGUCAAUAAAAUGUAGUUAAAAUGUGUGUAAACAUUAAAUAAAAGUGUAAGACAAAUGUGCAGAGAUAUUAUCUCUGUUGUUUGAAUUAAGGCUGUAUUACUUUUUGUCUUAGCUUUCCUAGAAAAAAAGAGCAAAGCGUAAUCAAAGAGUUGAUAUUAUUUAUCUUAUAUUUUCCUUUGAUAAUAUUUCCUUAAAAAUAGAUUAUUUAACAGAGAACUUUUCUGUUUCUGCCAAUAUUUUAAAAGAAAAACCAUGAUCUAUGAAGGCAAUUCAUAUUUGUGUUCAGAUUCCUUAUAUUGAUACAAAAUUGCCUUACUACUGAUAUGAUGAAGAAAAUGACAAAGUAAGAGUCUACAAUGGUGUGAUACUGCCCUUUUAUAAGGUAUUCGGCGAAUGAUGACGUGGUUUAUUAAUGUCUUGGUUUUUCCUUUUCUAGUAAACCUAUAAUAUUUUAUUUAUCUUUCCAUUGUCUCCUUCACAGGUUUCACUCCCCUCACCUAUAUCCAAGAAAAUGACUUUUAGAGGUAUUUGAGAACUGUAAAAAAUGUGUUCAAGCCCACUUCCUAUAGUUAAUGAGUCCCUCAACUCCCAUGUAUCAUUAAGAAAAUUGGUUGUUGAAUCCAGCAGCACAUCAAAAAGAUAAUUCACCACGAUCAAGUGGGCUUUAAACCUGGAUGCAAGGAUGGUUUAACAUACACGAAUCAAUAAAUGUGAUUCACCACAUAAACAGAACUAAAAACAAAAACCAUAUGAUCAUCUCAAUAGACACAGAAAAAAUAGUCAAUAAAUCCAACAUCCCUUUAUGACAAAAACACUCAACAAACCACGCAUUGAAGGAAAAUAGCCCAAAAUAAUAACAGCCAUCUGUGACAGACCCACAGCCAAUAUCAUAAUAAACUAGCAAAAGUUGUAUGCAUUCUUCCUGAGAACUGGAACAAGACAAGGAUGUCCCCUCUCAGCACUCCUAUUCAACAUAGUACUGAAAGCCCUAGCCAGAGCAAUCAGGCAAGAGAGAGAAAUGAAAGGCAUCCAAAUAGGAAAAGAAGAAGUCAAAUUAUCUCCGUUUACUGAAAAUAUAAUCCUGUACCUAAAAAACUUUAAAGGUUCCUCCAAAAAACUCCUAGGCCUGAUAAACUACUUGAGUAAAGUUUGAGGAUAUAAAAUCAACAUAGAAAAGUCAGUAGCAUUUCUAUACACCAAUAACAUUCAAGCUGAGAACCAAAUAAAAAACGCAAUCUUGGCUGGGUGUGGUGGCUCAUGCCCGAAAUCUCAGCACUUUGGGAGGCCAAGCGGGGAGGAUUGCUUGAGCCCAGAAGUUUAAGACCAGCCUUGGCAACAUAGUGAGACUCUGUCUACACAAAAAAAUUUAAAAAUUAGCUAAGCAUGGUAGCAUACACCUGUGGUCCCAGCUACUCAAGAAGAUGAGGUGGGAGAAUUGCUUGGACCUUGGAGGUUGAGGCUGCAGUGAGCUCUCAUCAUGCCACUGCACUCCACCCUGGACAACAGAGUGAGACCCUGUCUCAAAAAAAUAAAUAAAAGUUGUCCAAACAUGGUGGCUCACGCCUGUAAUCCCAGCACUUUGAGAGGCUGAGGCUGGUGGAUCACUUGAGGCCAGGAGUUCAAGACCAGCCUGGACAGCAUAGCAAGACCCUAUCUCUACUUAAAAAUAAAAAAACAAGAUGCCUGUAAUUCCAGCACUUUGGGAGGCCAAGGCAGGCAAAUUACUUGAGUACAAGAGUUCAAGACAAGUCUGAGCAACAUGGUGAAACCCCAAUCUCUACAAAAAAUACAAAAAUUAGCUGGUCACGCUGGCAUGCACCUGUAGUCCCAGCUACUUAAGAGGCUGAGGUGGAAGAAUCGCUUGAGUACAGGAGGUGGAGGCUACAGUGAGCCAAGAUUGCACCACUGCACUCCAGCCUGGGCGAUAGAGCGAAACUCUAUCUCGAUAAAAUAAAACAAAAUAAAAAAGUUAUUUUAAAAUUUCUAAAACAAGAAAAGAAAAUUGGCUGUCUUGGGACAGUAGCUAUGAAUCUGACUAGAUACAGGAUAAAUGGAUUUUAGUUUGAUUCCUUGAUUUUCAGCUUUGUCUGAUAUACAGGUGAAUGUAAAGAGCUCUACAGGUUUUCUAAGUCUGUGACAAAUACUUUUUUUUAUAGAUGUGAGCGUCCUUCAGCACUUGUCUAUUUCUUACCAUUGUGUUUUAUGGAAUGGCAUACUUUUUUUUAAAACAGAUUAUAAUAUAAUAUCAUCACAAAAUGAAAAUUACAUGAUAAUGAUUACAUGAUUAUUUCAUUAUGAAUUCUUUAUUGUGGCAAUUUGUAAAGAAAUGAGACAUUGUAAGUUUGCUUUUAUUAAGAUUACAACAAGUAAGCAGAAAUGCAAAAGUGAAAAUCAGGAGUGUGGAAACAACAUGCAAACGUUAACUAAGUGAAGAUAAAGUAUAUAUACAUAUACAACUACAUGAUAGAUAGAUAGAUAAAGAGAGAUAGAGGGAAAGAGAGGGAAAGAAGAGAAACUGGAAAAUUAGAGAGUAAGGGAAAGUAAAUUUUCUUAAUCCACAAAAACUUAUCUGAAGAAGUUGAUUCUAAUGUUCAAUAAAUGUAAACCCAUGAAAAUCACUAUGAA